CGCCUCCUCUGGCUCAGUCACACAGCGACGUAGAGGUGACUGGAGGUAUAUACUUGUCCUCACCUGGAUCAUGCUGAUGUGGCCCCAACCCCACCUCCCUACCCAUCCCCACCUCCCUACCCAUCCCCACCUCCCUACCCAUCCCCACCUCCCUACCCAUCCCCACCUCCCUACCCAUCCUAUGAUGUCCAAAGAAACCAGACAGAGCAAAUUGGCCGAGGCCAAGGAACAGUUGACAGACCAUCAUCCCCAGACCAACCCUAGUGUUGGUACAGCAGCAAGCGACACCAAAAAGAAGAAAAUAAAUAAUGGCACUAACCCUGAGACAACCACUUCUGGUGGUUGCCACUCGCCUGAGGAUGAACAGAAGGCAAGCCACCAACAUCAGGAAGCCCUAAGGAGGGAGCUAGAGGCCCAGGUUCAUACCAUACGAAUCCUUACAUGUCAGAAAACUGAGCUUCAGAUGGCACUCUACUACAGCCAGCAUGCUGUCAAGCAGUUGGAAGGAGAGGCCAGGGAUCUGAUCAGCCGCCUGCAUGAUUCAUGGAAGUUUGCAGGAGAGUUAGAGCAGGCUCUCUCUGCUGUCGCUACACAGAAGAAGAAGGCGGAUAGGUACAUUGAGGAGUUAACAAAGGAGAGGGACGCCCUGAGUCUGGAACUGUACAGGAACACCAUAACUGAUGAGGAGCUGAAGGAGAAAAAUGCCAAACUACAAGAAAAACUUCAACUUGUAGAAUCUGAAAAGUCUGAGAUCCAGCUCAACGUAAAGGAGCUAAAAAGGAAACUGGAGAGGGCCAAGCUCCUGCUGCCACAGCAGCAGCUGCAGGCGGAGGCUGACCACCUGGGUAAGGAGCUGCAGAGUGUGUCAGCAAAGCUCCAAGCCCAGGUGGAAGAGAACGAGUUGUGGAACCGCCUGAACCAGCAACAGGAGGAGAAGAUGUGGAGGCAGGAGGAGAAGAUACAGGAGUGGGAGGAGAAGAUACAGGAGCAGGAGGAGAAGAUACGGGAGCAGGAGGAGAAGAUACGGGAGCAGGAGGAGAAGAUGCGGAGGCAGGAGGAGAUGAUGUGGGAGAAGGAGGAGAAGAUGCGGAGGCAGGAGGAGAUGAUGUGGGAGAAGGAGGAGAAGAUGCGGAGGCUGGAGGAGAUGAUGUGGGAGAAGGAGGAGAAGAUACGGGAGCUGGAAGAGAAGAUGCACGAGCAGGAGAAGAUACGGGAGCAGGAAGAGAAGAGGCAGGAGGAGGAGAAGAUACGCGAGCAGGAGAAGAGGCAGGAGCAGGAGGCGAAGAUGUGGAGGCAGGAGGAGAAGAUACGGGAGCAGGAAGAGAAGAUACGGGAGCAGGAGAAAAAGAUGUGGAGGCAGGAGGAGAAGAUUCACGAGCAGGAGAAGAUACGGGAGGAGGAGAAGAGGCAGGAGCAGGAGGAGAUGUGGAGGCAGGAGGAGAAGAUAAGGGAGCAGGAGGAGAUAUGGAGGCAAAAGGAGAAGAUGCACGAGCAGGAGAAGAUACGGAAGCAGGAGGAGAAGGUGUGGAGGCAGGAGGAGAAGAUGCACGACCAGGAGGAGAAGAUACGGGAGCAGGAGGAGAAGAUGUGGAGGCAGGAGGAGAAGAUAAGGGAGCAGGAGGAGAAGAUACGGGAGCAGGAGGAGAAGAUACGAGAGCAGGAGGAGAUGAUGCAGGAACAGGAAGAGAAGAUGGGGGAGCAGGAAGAGAAGAUGCAAGAACAGGAGAAGAUGCGGAGGCAGGAGGAGAAGAUAAGGGAGCAGGAGGAGAAGAUACGGGAGCAGAAGGAGAAGAUACGAGAGCAGGAGGAGAAGAUAUGGGAGCAGGAGGAGAAGAUACGAGAGCAGGAGGAGAUGAUGCAGGAACAGGAAGAGAAGAUGUGGGAGCAGGAGGAGAAGAUGUGUGAGCAGGAAGAGAAGAUGCAAGAACAGGAGGAGAAGAUGCGGAGGCAGGAGGAGAAGAUGUGGGAGCAGGAAGUGAGGCUGCGGCAGCAGGAGGAGAAGAUGCAGGAACACCAGGUGGAGCUGAAGAGCCAAGAGGCUGAGUCUGCAGCAGCAGCGAGACCAUUACCUGGGUCACCUGCAGCAGAGCACCUGGAAGCUGCCAUCUAAUGAGCACAUGACAAGAAGGCAAAGACAAUAAACAUGUAAAAGCCGGCAGCAAGGCCUGGAGAAGAGUAAGCCGCCAUGUGACUGUUUAGAAUAUAGUCUGAGCACAAACCUGAAAAAAAAAUUUUAUUUAUUUUAAAUUGUGGCAAAAUACUGGCCAGGCAUGGUAGCUCACGCCUGUAAUCCUAGCAAUUUGGGAGGCCGAGGUAAAUGGAUGACCUGAGGUCAAGAGUUCAAGACCAGCCUGGCCAAUACAAAAAUUAGCCGGGCAUGGUGGCGCAUGCCUGUAAUCCCAGCUACUUGGGAGGCUGAGGCAGGAGAAUCGCUUGAACCUGGGAGGCAGAGGUUGCAGUGAGCUGAGAUCGUGCCACUGCACUCAAGCCUGGGUGACAGAGCGAAACUCCGUCUCAAAAAAAAAAGUUUCUUCCUUACAUGUAUGUUUCUAUUAGUUUUCUUCUUGGUCUUUCUCAUUUAGUCUUGUGUUGUCUUUUGACAUUCAUAGUAAACUUUUAUCUGCCUCCA